GAGGGGACGGCCGGCAGGCGUGGGGUCCGCGGCGUCAGGGCUCCUUCCUCCCGUCCGCUCCAUCCUGCAACCCGUAGCCCGGGCGGGGUCUCGCUGCCCCCUCCCCGAACACAGCCGCCUUUUCCUCCCUCCCCAACCCCGAGCGCCUCCCUUCCCGAAUGCGGGAGUCCAUAGUGCACGGGAAGCCUCUUCCCCUCCCCACCGAGGCUGCCCGACGCCCCUUCCACCCUCCGACCCCCCGCAACCAUCCCUCAAAUGCCCCGGCGGCCAGCAGGGCUGGGGUGGGCGCAGGAGAACCAGGGGUCCUGCCCGCAUGCAGGGGUUUGGGGUCGGUGUGGCCGAAUGAACGCGCGGGUUCAGACGAGCCUGUGAUGCCCCCGCUUUCCAUCUCCUCGCGACCUGGCCCCAGAAGACAGUCUGAGAGGCCGGUGGCCGCGGAUCCUGGACGCGCUUCCCUCCUGCCUGUGGUUUCCCUUUAUUCCGGCAGCGCUGGCUGCGUGGUGAAGCCCUCAGGACCCUCCGCGUGGGUUGGGCGGGUGACGUGGAUGAGGGACAACGUGGUGAGGUCCCCGUCGUGGCGAAGAGUGACCAGUAGGUGCCCAGGGCCCAACCCUCCUCUGCACCCGAGAGAAACCAUCUCCUCUGCAGCAGCCCCCACCUGGACGCUCUGGAGUCCUCCCCACCUCCCUCCCCAGUGGGGCGCACAGCAUUCUUGCUACCCUGAAAGGCAGACGGGAGGCACAGGGUGGCAGAGGGGGGCCAGGUCUGAGAUUCCAGAUGGAAGGGACCAUGGGGCUCCACCCCACCACCACUGUAGGCAGGGGACUGGCAGGUGUACACCCUUACUCCCGCGGGGCCCAGGGACACAGCCACCCUCCUUUGAGGCCCUGGCCCUCAGGACCCUGCCACAGCGAGGUCUGUGCCUCCCCAGUGACCAGUGGUCACCGGGCUCGGGGUCACCCAGCUGCUUCCACAUGUGA